GUCAAGACAGAGGCUUCCUUACAGAACUCCAAAGAUGGUGAAAGGAACCUCAUUUAUAUUUCCUUACCUAACAAGAAAACAGAAUAGGUUUUCUGAUGAACCUGGAUGGAACAACACAAUCUAACAACGGUGAAUGAAUUCAUUCUUACGGGAAUCACAGAUAUCGCUGAGCUGCAGGCACCAUUAUUUGCAUUGUUCCUCAUGAUCUAUGUGAUCUCAGUGAUGGGCAAUUUGGGCAUGAUUGUCCUCACCAAGUUGGACUCCAGGUUGCAAACCCCUAUGUACUUUUUUCUCAGACAUCUGGCUUUCAUGGAUCUUGGUUAUUCAACAACUGUGGGACCCAAAAUGUUAGUAAAUUUUGUUGUGGAUAAGAAUAUAAUUUCUUAUUAUUUUUGUGCAACACAGCUAGCUUUCUUUCUUGUGUUCAUUGGUAGUGAACUUUUUAUUCUCUCAGCCAUGUCCUACGACCUCUAUGUGGCCAUCUGUAACCCUCUGCUAUACACAGUAAUCAUGUCACGAAGGGUAUGUCAGGUGCUGGUAGCAAUCCCUUACCUCUAUUGCACAUUCAUUUCUCUUCUAGUCACCAUAAAGAUUUUUACUUUAUCCUUCUGUGGCUACAACGUCAUUAGUCAUUUCUACUGUGACAGUCUCCCUUUGUUACCUUUGCUUUGUUCAAAUACACAUGAAAUUGAAUUGAUAAUUCUGAUCUUUGCAGCUAUUGAUUUGAUUUCAUCUCUUCUGAUAGUUCUUUUAUCUUACCUGCUCAUCCUUGUAGCCAUUCUCAGGAUGAAUUCUGCUGGCAGACAAAAGGCUUUUUCUACCUGUGGAGCCCACCUGACAGUGGUCAUAGUGUUCUAUGGGACUUUGCUUUUCAUGUACGUGCAGCCCAAGUCCAGUCAUUCCUUUGACACUGAUAAAGUGGCUUCCAUAUUUUACACCCUGGUUAUCCCCAUGUUGAAUCCCUUGAUCUAUAGUUUACGAAACAAAGAUGUAAAAUAUGCCCUACGAAGGACAUGGAAUAACUUAUGUAAUAUUUUUGUUUAAAUUUUGUACAAUAUGAUUCCUAUAAAUUAGGUUAUGGGCAUGAAUUUUUGCUCUGCAUACUUCCAGAAGACAUAACAAGCAUAACUGAUUCAACAUAUAUUUACAUAUGUCUCAUACAUGAUAGGCUCUUCUAAUUGCUAUACAUAGAUUAAUAAACAAAAUAGUAGAAAUCUUUGCCUUCCUUGAUGGAUAGAUGAAUUGUAUUCACAAUAAGUCCAUUUUAUAUAACAGUAGAAUGUGCACGAUGGAUAUAGACAAAGAAAAAAGGGAGACAAGGAAAGCUAGUAUGCUGGGUGGCAGUAGGAAACAGUGGUCAUUACAGAAGGGAGUUACGAGGAUUCCAGUGUUUUUUAUCUGCUACUGGAAUAAAAUUUACAGUGUGUGUGCUUCUGUAUGUUUCUGUUUGUGUGUUUUUGUGUAUAUAAGCAUUUUCCUUCUGUUUUAGCCUUCAUACUUUUUGCUUGUAUAUUCUGACAUUGCAUUUAAUACUGGUUGUUUAGAUGAUAUGUGAUGAUUUUAAGUCUUACAGAUGUGCUCGAAUAAUUACUAUUCCGAAUAUUAGGAUCCUACUAUUUCCUUAUCAAUGUUUUUAUUUCCACAUAGAAGUCUGUUAACCGAACAUACUUUGUAGCUCAAUAAUCGGUAAAUUCUGAUUAGCACCUGAUUUUGUUUCAGUUAGCCCAUUCUGUUUACAUGAGUAGAUAUAUCAAUUAUGCUUAAGUUUAGAAGACAUCCAUAGAAAUUCUCAGGUUUAUUCUUUCUCUCUAGUUGUUCUUGCUUAAUAACUGCCUUUUUCACAGAUUUUCCCGUUAUUUAUCUAAAAAAAAGUAAUAAACUGUGGUUAAAAUUUGUGUUCCAGUUGUUUUUACAUCUUUGAGGAGGGGGACCAUUCUAUGAUGAAUUAACUUUGUAGUCUCUCACUGAGUUGACAAUCCAUAAUUUUUAUCAAUAUGCACUAUAUCGAAUGCACUAUAUUUUCAUUUACUUCACUGUUUGAUUGCAUCAGUUGAUUUUUCUACUUGUACAAAGCAAAUAAAAGUAAUAAAAUGCACUACACCAUACUGUAUCUAUCUGCUGGCUAUUACAGAUGUCCUUUGACAGUUACAGACCUUCACCAUGCAAGUGAGGUCUGAUCUGUAUGCAAUGAUAUCGUUAUCUUGCCUUUUAAACAUGGUUGCUUUCCUUAACUCCAUAUGUUUUCUUAUGUAUUUUGAUUUCCUUUAUUCUUUUUAAUAAUCCUAAGAAUUUAUUGAAAGUAUCAGAGUCUACAAUAUUUUCUUGGUUCACCAUCAUAAAAUAAAAUCCCAUGUGCAGCCAAAGAAACACUAAUGAAUAUAUCUCAUUGGAAUAAAUUAAACAUUGCAUAGCACAUUGUCAUGUGAGGAUAAAUAUUA